AAUUAAAAAAAUUCGACAUGUUUUCUUGGAAUUUAUUUUUGACUUUAAUUUUGUGCCUACAUACCUAAAUAGGUUAUAUAUCCAAUAUGUUUUUAGGUUCUUUGGUGUUGGAUACUACUUUUUAUGGGGGAAAAUUUUUUUUUUACUUGAAAUACAAGGAAUGGAUCCUUUCCUCCCUCCACCCCUAUGUCACUAAAUGGGAGUAAAUUGUACUUAAGAUAUGCCCAAGCUUUAGCACCCAGAAUGUAGUCUUUAAAAUAUUAUUUCCUACUAAAAGGGGUUCCUUGGAGAAAUGUCUGGUUCUAGGCCUAAGGCAGGAUUUGUAGAAGGUAAGUCUGGAACUUCUUGUCCUAGCAGGAAGCUAGGAGGUUAUCUUCAUUUACUAGGUUUAUGUCAAAAGGGCUUAGGAGCUUUGUAGAGGGUCCCUCAAGACCAUUCCCACAUUUCAUGAUUUCCAAGAUUGACUCUCAGGACUCAAGUCAUUUUAUUCACAGUUAUAGUUUAUUGCAAUGAGAUGAUACAAGGCAAAAUCAGCAAAGCGAAAGGCAUAUGGAAUGAAGUCUGGAAGAAACCAAGCUCAAGCUUGCAAGAAUCCUCUCCCAGUAGAAUUGGAAAAGAUGCCAUUAAUUCUCCAGUAAUGAGUUGUGUGCACAGCCUCAGAUUAGCCCCUAAUGAGAUUUUAAGGGCUUCUCCGAUUAUUCCUGAGCAUGCGUAUAGCACUGGGUACACAUCCCUUUGCAUAAAUAUGACCUUCUGGAUUCCCAGGAAGUUGUUGGAGCUUUUCAGAGUCUUUUAUGGACAUCUCAUUCCCCAGCUUUUCUUUUCUGGGUUUUUUGUUUGUUUGUUUUUGAGGUAAGGUUUGUUUGUUUGUUUUUGAGAUGGAGUCUCGCUCUGUCAUCCAGGAUCAAGUACAGUGGUGCAAUCUCAGCUCACUGCAACCUCUGCCUCCUGGGUUCAAACGAUUCUCCUACUUCAGCCUCCCAAGUAGCUGGGAUUACAGGUGCUCGCCACCAUGCCCGGCGAAUUUUUUGUAUUUUUAGUAGAGACAGGGUUUCACCAUGUUAGCCAGGAUGGUCUUGAUCUCCUGACCUCGUGAUCCACCCGCCUCAGCCUCCCAAAGUGCUGGGAUUACAGGUGUGAGCCACCACGCCCGGCUUGGGCAGUUCUUUUUCUGAUCUUCCCUGAGAUUACUCAUGUCAUUUGAUUGGGACUGUUAUUUAAGAUGGCUUCACUCACACAUUUGUUGGGUAGUGCUGGCUGUUGGCUGGCCUAUGUCUAUUCAUUAGGCUAGCUUUGGCUUCUUCACAUGGCUGCUAGAUUUUAAAAGUAGAAAGAAGGGCAAGCUCCAGUAUGCAAGCACUUUUCAAACCUUUGCAUUACGUGGGAUAGUUUCGCAUUCCUAUAAAUGUUUUUGAGCUCUGCUCUGGGAUGCAGUUACAUUUAUUUGAAAAUAGUUCCAGAUUUUGAUUUUACAGAUCACCUGAGUUCAGGAGUUCGAGACCAGCCUGGCCAAUAUGGUGAAACCCCGCUUCUACUAAAAAUACAAAAAUUAGCUGGGCGUGGUGGUGGGCACCUAUAAUCCCAGCUACUUGAGAGGCCGAGGCUGGAGAAUCACUUGAACCCAGGAGGCGGAGGUUGCAGUGACUGGAGAUUGCGCCAUUGUGCUCCAGCCUGGUUGACAAGAGCGAAAUUCCGUCUCAAAAAAAAAAAAAUUUUAAGAUUUAAUAGAUAGUACUGGAUCUGUGUUCACUGUAGGGGUAGUAAGUCCCCAUUACUUAGGAAGAACUCUUAUGUGUACUUGACCCCAUCCUCAAUGGAAUUGGUGAGAAGCGGCACUAUUUCUGGCCCUGUAAUUGGAAAAUAUUUAACUCUUAACAAAUGAAUUCCCCACUUGAACUCUGCCGAAUUCCUGUGCCACCUCCUCCUUUAGAAAACUGAUCUUAAUACAGAGAUAAAAGAGGAGUAGAAGGUAAAAGAAAAUGCUGGGAACUGACCGUUGUGUUGUGGAAGAAUGGUUAUCAGAAUUCAAGGCAUUACCUGACACUCAGAUCACCAGUUAUGCAGCAACUUUACACCGGAAAAAAACACUUGUACCAGCCCUCUAUAAAGUUAUUCAAGAUUCAAAUAAUGAGCUCCUGGAGCCUGUCUGCCAUCAGCUGUUUGAGCUCUAUCGUAGCUCAGAGGUUCGACUUAAGAGGUUCACACUGCAGUUCUUGCCAGAAUUGAUGUGGGUUUAUUUACGGCUUACAGUUAGCCGAGACAGACAGAGUAAUGGUUGCAUUGAAGCACUUCUGUUAGGAAUUUACAAUUUGGAAAUCGCUGAUAAAGAUGGGAACAAUAAAGUUCUGUCUUUCACUAUCCCCUCCUUAUCCAAGCCUUCAAUAUACCAUGAACCUUCAACAAUUGGAUCCAUGGCUUUGACAGAAGGGGCAUUGUGUCAGCAUGAUCUCAUCAGAGUUGUUUAUAGUGAUCUUCAUCCUCAGAGGGAAACAUUCACUGCACAGAACCGGUUUGAAGUCCUGAGUUUUCUCAUGCUGUGUUAUAAUUCUGCUAUUGUAUAUAUGCCUGCCUCAUCUUACCAAUCUCUUUGUCGGAUGGGUUCCAGGGUUUGUGUGAGUGGCUUUCCACGGCAACAUGAAAAACACUGGAAAGAACUCUGUGGUCGAAUAGUAUUGGAUCCUGAAUUUAUGGUGCAACUUCUCACAGGGGUUUAUUAUGCCAUGUAUAAUGGACAGUGGGACCUUGGCCAGGAAGUUCUUGAUGAUAUCAUUUAUAGAGCCCAGCUAGAGCUUUUUUCUCAACCACUAUUGGUUGCCAAUGCCAUGAAAAACUCAUUACCAUUUGAUGCUCCUGAUUCUACACAAGAAGGCCAGAAAGUCCUUAAAGUUGAAGUCACUCCAACAGUGCCGAGGAUUUCUCGGACUGCAAUUACAACAGCUUCAAUCCGUCGUCAUAGAUGGAGAAGAGAAGGUGCUGAGGGUGUAAAUGGAGGAGAGGAGUCUGUAAACCUGAAUGAUGCAGAUGAAGGAUUUUCAUCAGGGGCUUCCCUCAGCAGUCAGCCAAUUGGGACCAAACCAUCCUCCUCUUCUCAGAGGGGAAGCUUAAGGAAAGUAGCAACUGGGCGUUCAGCCAAGGAUAAAGAAACAGCCUCUGCCAUCAAAUCCAGUGAGAGCCCUCGAGAUUCAGUAGUUCGCAAGCAGUAUGUACAGCAACCAACUGAUCUUAGUGUAGAUUCAGUUGAGCUGACACCAAUGAAGAAACACCUGAGCCUGCCUGCUGGCCAGGUGGUGCCAAAAAUCAAUAGCUUAAGUCUAAUCCGGACAGCCAGUGCUUCCUCAAGUAAAUCAUUUGACUAUGUAAAUGGCAGUCAAGCAAGUACCAGCAUUGGGGUUGGCACUGAGGGAGGUACUAAUUUAGCAGCCAACAAUGCUAAUCGAUACUCAACUGUCAGUCUGCAGGAAGACCGGCUAGGUCAAGCUGGCGAAGGUAAAGAGCUCCUCAGCCCAGGAGCCCCCUUGACCAAGCAGUCUCGAUCCCCAAGUUUCAAUAUGCAGCUAAUAUCCCAGGUGUAGUUUUGACAUCCUCCCUCAUCUUUCUGCUUACCUUUUAAACUGAACAUUUCAUUGUGCAAGAAGACACUUCAUCCCACAUUGUGAAAAUAUUGGUCACUGUUAUCAGAUUUCAUUUAGUUUAGGUAUCUUCAUACUGUAUUUUGUAUCAAAACAGCAAUAAGGUUUUCUUUAUCCCUCUUUCCUACAUCUUCUCUUCACCUAUCCCUUGUAAAUGUGUUUGUGAAGCAGUAUAAAAUGGUUGCCUUUUCCAUGCCUUCCUUUCUCCUUGGGUGAUGUGCAAUCCAUCGUAGGCUGAUCGGUCCCAUUUCAACACUGUGAGACUGAGGGUACAUUAGAGGAAAUGGUGUAUAUGAUCCCUAUGAAACGAUUCUUUGGCUUUUGUUUAAAAACAAAACGGGUUUGUUCUCAUAAUCUAUAGAACUAUGAAGAUUACUGGAUCAUAUUUUUUUCUCUUAACCAGGAGUGCCUCAGAGAUUCUGCUAUGACUUUGGACUUCUCUGAGUCUGUGCAAUCAUUUUCUGGAGAAGCAUGGGGAAAGGUGGUAGACUGCUGCACUUUUUCAUUAAAAUGAGGGUAGCUCUUUCUCCACCCCCCCAUCUCCUUUAUCCCGAAGACAUAAAUGUUCAAUUACGGAGGCAUUUAAAUCAAGUUGUGACCACCUCCAUUGGAGGGCAGGACUCUUGAUUGUGUAAUUGAUAAUGCACUUUCUCAAUGGCUGUAUAGUCAUUAUUAACGUGUCUUCCCUCUUCCCCACAAGGACAUAUAAGGUCAUUUCUGUCCUUCAAGUUUGGCCAACUAACAAAUCAGAAUCUGAGGGGCAUGUUCUAUUUCCCAGGAAUGAUUGACACUUUGGUGCUGGGGUUUUGUGGGGGCGGGGGGUAGUUUUUGUUUAGCUUUUGUGGAGAUUGUGUGUGUGAGAGGAGAUUUGAUUUUUUUUUCUUCUUUUCCUUUGUGAGCUGAUGGCUGAAGUGUAACAGUACAUCUUCAGGUAAAGAGAGGGAUUUCUCAAUCUACUUUCUGUUAUGUCAGACUAUAAGAGAAACCCUUUCAGCUGCUUUCUAGAUGUACCUAAAUUCAGUCAGACAUUUUGGAUUAAGAAACCUAAAGUCCUGAUACAUUACAUACUCCAAGGAAAUAUAUCAGGGACAGACAAUUGGCUGAAACACUGAUACUUCAAUGUGACACAUUUUUAUAGAACAUUUCUACCAGGGGGUACUGACCUUGAUUUCUCCUACAAGGACCACACUGCCUUUGUGUUUAAUGUAAUGCAAUUUGUGUACCUUCUAAUCAUAUAUCUGCAGUUCCUCAUUUUUAUAAAACUUUGAUAUCAUGCCAGUAAGCUAGAUGUUGAAUGUAUGUAAGUAGCAUUUGGUAACUGCUAAGAGGUUACAAAAACAUUAUUGGUAAAAAAAAUUUCCUUAGUUCUGAUCUGGUUGGAUAAGAUUUUAUCAUAACUUUUCUGGGUCUCAGGCUCUGAUGUUUGAAAAAGAAGGGAAUAUAUUGGGUUUUAAAAAAGUGUAUUGUGACUUAAACUGUUAUAAGUUAUCCUUCCACAGAAUACAUCAGAGCUAUCAGUGCUUUGUACAUUUAGAUGUUUUUACUUGAUUAUUGUUUAAGAAAAAUAUACUGAAUUUAUAGAAAGCAAGUAUUCUCCUAAUUAGCAAAAGUUAAAAUUUUAUCUCUACCAUUAAAAUUACAAUAGAUUUUGAUAAAUAACCAGAAAAAACGCCUUUUUUUUUUUCACACCUAGCAAUCCUCCCGUUUUUAUUGUAAGGACUUUCUUUUUUCCCUAAGAGACUUUCUGUUAGACUCUUUAUAUAUGAGAUGCUUGUUUAAAUAUGGUGGUCUGUAACAUUUUUCCAGCUCAUGUGAAAAUGGAAAACUAGAACCUGAACUAGUAUCUACAACAUUGCCAAAGUCCAGGGUAAAGCUAAAAGUUGAUAAGUAGACAAUUUAUUGUUUUGUGUGUGUCUGUGUGUGUGUGUGUGUGUGUGUGUGUGUGUGUAUGGUGUGUAUAUGUAUAUAUCACAAAGUUGUAUUUUAAAUAUUUUAAAUACCCUUUCUUUUAAUUUAAGGGAUGUCAAAUAAAUGAAAGGAGUUUAAAAAUAGCCAAAAUAAAUGAGCUAUAAAGGCCCAUAACAUACUAAAACAGGCAGUUUCAGGUAUGUAAGGAAAGGAACAUUAUACUUACCUAGAAAGUGAGAUCUAAAAAAAAAUUAAAAAUAAAUAAAAAAUAAAAAAGAAAGUGAGAUCUUGGCUAUGGCUGGAGGUCAGUCACUUUAUGGCAUAAAUUAUUUGGGAGGUAAAAAGACUGUUUUCAAUUCAAAUUGUGCAUUUAUUGGCAUCUAAAUCUAGCAUGAUUUUGGUUAGAGCACAAAAGAAAUACCACAUAAUACCAAAUCACAGCAAAUGUUAGAAUUAAUACAACAAAAUUUUCCUUUGGCUAGAAAUCUUAUGUUAUACCUGAAAAAUUGGUUUUAAAAAAUGUUCAUCUUGGCCGGGCACGGUGGCUCACGCCUGUAAUCCCAACACUCUGGGAGGCUGAGGUGGGUGAAUCAUGAGGUCAGGAGUUCGAGACCAGCCUGGCCAACAUGGUGAAACCCUGUCUCUACUAAAAAUACAAAAAAUUAGCUGGGCGUGGUGGCAGGCGCCUGUAAUCCCAGCUACUCGGGAGGCUGAGGCAGGAGAAUCUCUUGAACCUGGGAGGUGGAGGUUGCAGUGAGCCAAGAAUGCACUACUGUACUCCAGCCUAGGCAACAGUGCAAGACUCCAUCUCUGAAAAAAAAAAAAAAAAAAAAAAAAAAAGUUCAUCUUAGAGGAUUUUAUUUAUCUGUAUGUAUAUACAUAUAUGUUUGUAUGUAUACAUACCCACAUUAACAUUUUAUGACCCUGUAACAUUUGUUUUCUAUUCUUUUAGGUGAUGUGAAUUGACCUCAGUGAAGAAACAUUUCAUUUAGUCUAAGCCUUGCAUUCAGGGUCUUACAACAGAUUUCUUGUGCAAGAAUUAUUAUUAGUUAAAAUGGAAGGUGUUAGUUUAACAAACUGAGAGUCAAAUUUUCUAAGUUUUUAAAUAUGCAUUUUAACAUGCAUUAUUUUUGGCAUUUAAUUUAAAAUAGUUUUGUUUCAUGUAUACAACAGCUGUUACAGAUAUAUGCCAGCAAUAUUCAUACUUUUUUAACAAGCUUUUGUUAUAUAUUUUCUAAUCUCCAUAAAAGUCUAAUCAUCUAUGAAAAAGAUAUUUAGGGAGAAAAUACUUGUUUUCUGUAAUAAAACAAUUAGGUUGGUGCCAUGUAUGCCAAGUUGGAUAAAAGAAUACAAAGAAACAGCUGAAGGUUUUGGGAGCUCGCUCUGACAUUAAUUACUAGAAAGCAAACUAAAAUGCAAAGUGAAUAGUUAACUCAGAAGAUUUGAAUUUUUUGAAAUAGGGUCUCACUCUGUCCUCUAGGCUAGAGUGCAGUGGCACUAUCACGGCUCACUGCAGCCUCAACCUCCCUGGGCUCAGGUGAUCUUCCCACCUCAGCCUCUGGAGUAGCUGGAACUCCAGGCAUGCACCACCACACCUGGCUAAUUUUUGUAUUUUUAGUAGAGACGAGGUUUUGCCAUGUUGCCCAGGCUGGUCUCGAACUCCUGGGCUUAAGAGAUCCACCCACCUGGCCUCCCAGAAGUGCUAGGAUUACAGACAUAACUACCACACCUGGCCUGAAGAUUUUUAAAUGUGAAAAUAUUUUAAGAAGCUAAGGGGAAAAUCGUUAUUUUAAAAUCCUGAUCCCCUUAACUUUACCCCUUACCAUUCCCCUUACCUUUCCAAUUCACUUUUGUCUAUUUAUUAUAGAAUCAGAAUUGUGCUAAGAAGAAACCCUGGAGAUAAUCUAGCUAGUCUCCCACUCCCUCACCCCAACCUUCAUCCUCAAGAAACAGAGGCUCAGAGGUUGUGGUGUGAUCAAGAUCAUAUACCUAAAGCAGAGCCAGAAUCAAACCCAGUCUCCCAUGGGUUUGGGGAGGCAGUGGGUUGUUAACUCCAUUUUUGCAGUUUCUUUAUAGUUCUGGUCUAGUAGUUGGUGAAUACAACACAUUAAGAAAAGUGUUAAAUCCAGAAAAAAUGUAGAGUAAUCUAGAUGGGGAAAUGUUGGAAAUGUUAAGUAUAUCUACAGAUGUAAGGAUCAAUACAUUAUUCUAAUUUAUGCCUUACUAUUUUCUGCCACAUAACAGUUGUAUGCUGCCAUUUUAUAGUUGAAUACAUUUGUUGGGAUUUAUUUAAAUAUAAAAUAAACCCUGUGAAAUGGCUUUGAUCAGUGUUUUCUAGUUAUUUUAAAGUAAUUUUUGAGUCAGCCAGCUUUCAGUCACCAGUGUGGCAAGCUAAUUAUAUUGCACAAUAGAGUAUUGCAAAGUAAAGAUUAAAUAAAUUUGAUUCCAUUACUUUUUAAUGUAGAAAGAGACUGAAUCUUAUGCUUAGAGCAAAUGCAAGCAAUAUUUCCUUAUAUGAUUGAAAAAGGUUCUAUAGUGUGAAGCUUAUGAUUCCAUAAUGGAACAGUGACCAUGAUGUCAUUUAAAGUGUGUAUAUACCAUAUAAAAUGUCUUAAAUGCGGUAGUCUCAGCUAUAUAAGCUCAGUAUUUCCAGUCUGUAUUCUCAGAUUCCAUCUAGUAGCUUUAAAUUAAUUAAAAUUGUUUAUUAGACACUGGAAUACUGAGAAUAACUUCUUUCAGAUUGUUUUGUUUGCACCACUUUUGUGAAUAUUUUAAUGAAGUGGAGUCCAUUUUUGAGUACUUCAGUUGUUGACAAUCAGUUGUCUCGUUUAAAUCUCUGCAUGUUCAUUUGUAAAUAAAAAAUGUAGUACCUGUCUUUAGGGGUAGUCCCCUAUUUAUUACAAACACUGGCAAGGAAUAUCUGUCCAUUUCUGACCUUGGAUUACAAAGUAUGUUUUGGGUUUUUCCUUUUUUAAUCAGUAUUUCAGUUACAUCUUUGUUUUCAGCUUUAAAAAGUUUAACGGGUCAUGCCAAUGAUCAGAAAAUCUGUAAGAAUUUUAGAGCAAUUUUUCUAUGUACAGCUAUGUUAAACAGUCUGAACAUGAGACUUUUUCUUUCAAGUUGAAGAUUAUUGUCAUCGUUUUACCACUAAGUUGGUUGAGACACUUACUUGUAAUACUUUAAUUUUUUUAAAGUGUUUUUAGAAACAAGUUGUUUGAAAACCAAUUAGAAAUUAGAAUAUUUGCCAGAUUAUAAGCAGAUGGAAUGCAGUGUAAAACUGUUAACAAUGCUAAUAAAAUUAUGAGUCAUCAGAUUGGUACAGUUUUCCCUGCCAAGAUGGUCAUAUUGAUAAUGUAAGACAAAUUUUAGUAUUACUUGCAUUAUGUGUACCUAAUAGGUAUAUCAUACUGGUACUGAGCAUAUAUAGAAAAUACUAUUCAUAGAGGAGUCAUCACCACCCAACCUCCUUGCCUGUGUAGGCAUAUUUCUUCUGAACCUGACCACACAAGUACAACAUUUUGGUAACUUCAGUCUUUUCAGUAUUUUUGUAAUCUUAGCCAUAGUCCUAUGAGAAAUGUACAUAAGAGCAAACAAUUCAGGAUAGAAAUUAGCAGAAAGCUGGGAAUGAUGUGAAAUAACUGGCAGCAUAGUACAGAAAUGUAAGGUAUAUGUUUUGCUUCUGGAUUUUUAGAAAUUGUGCUAAUCAUGUUUACAAAUUAAGGCAUAUUCAGAUGUCUGCUAUUAUGUUUAAUAUUGAUUUGAUAAAAAAAUGGAAUUAGGUGUAGCUUAGAGUAUAAAUGAGUCUUUUUAAAAAUGUGUAUCUGGAAGUAGGGCUAAUAAAGAAAUCCUUUUAUUUUCAAAGAAAUGAACUUAAUUGGACAACUCAUCCCCAAUUACAGAAUUGAUAUCAAUAUGGUUUGCUGUAUUUGAGUAUAAACAGCUCAGUGUUAAUUAUAUCAAAGGAAGUUCUUUACAUCUUCAUUGAUUACAAAAUUUACCAAAGAAAAUGUAUCUACCAAAUAUAAUUUUUAAAGUACUUGUUAAGGAAUGAGGCCUCUUUAACAUAUAAAGUAUCUUAAAAAUAUUCUCUGACCUGGAAAAUAGGUUUACAGUAGCUACAAGAUUCCAUUUUAGGUUUUCUUAUGUCAAUAAAUGUCAAUAUUUUACACUUCCAGCAAAAGUACCCGUUAAAGCUAAAUCUAAAUAUUAUUCCUCAUAGCACAGUUUCUGGUCUCCUUAAAUUAAGGAUCCUACUCAUCAGGAUUGAAUAAAAAGGGGGAAAUUCCUAAAAUUGGUAUAUUGUAUAAUAUUGUGGGUUAAGUAAAAUUUAGGGGGGCAUUAUGGAAAUGUACCUAUUUUAAAGGGCAGUGGCAAUUACUAUAAUAUUGGUUAAACUGGUAAAGUUUGUUAAAUAAUUUAUGUCCAUGAUCAUUCUGAGUGUUUUUUUUCUUUGCAGAAAAACAGGAUUGGGUUAAGAAAAGCUAAAAUACUCAUUUUUUUAAAAUGUAUAGCCCAAUAAGAACUAAAUGAUUUAUUUCAAAAGUUAAAUAAUUUUUUUUGGAAAUCAUGGAAUGUAUUUGCAUAUUGAUGUUCCAAACAGGUUUUAUGUAUUGUUUUUUAUAGCAGGGAGUAGUUGAAAAGUAAUGAGUAUAUUGAUUAGCUGUCUUGGAAAGAGAGGAUUGGCUUUCUAACAAUCACUGAUACAGGUUUGGGUUUGGGGGGGUUUGUUUGUUUGUUUUUAAGUUUUAUCAUCCAUACUGAAUUGAGAGAUAUGCUCCAUGUUUAAAAAUAUUUGUAAUAAGUUCAUCUACUUGACACUGAAUCUUUUUUAUUCUUACUCUAAAAUUAUUCUGGCUUUACAUUCAGUUUAAGUGGUUAAGUGAAACAGUUUUUAGGGUGCAAAAAUUAUUUUCCCACUGUUUUUCUCAUGAUAAUUUGAGUCUCCUGAGCUAUAAUUUCUGAAGGAUUUUUACUACUUUGGCAUUAUGUAAUCUGAUCUCUGUCACAAUGAUAUUAAAUAAGAACUAUCUCACUUUCAUAUGUUUGCUUCAUAAAAGGAUAUGGAAUGUACACAUCAGCUCUUUUUUUUUUUUUAAACUAGCAUCAACCUAUAACUUGGUAUAAACUUCCCAAGUAUUUAGAGAAUAGUGCUGGUGAAAAUUUAAAUAGGAUAGGCAUAUAGAAAUUAUGACUUGUAUUGAGUGAUGUCCUUUCAACCUAGGACUAGUGACAACCUUCAUUUUUUCAGAGCUGAAGAAAAAACCGUGAAUUUAAGAUCAUAUUUAUUGGUGCAUGUAAGCCAUUAUCCUGUCUUAAUGAACCGAUUAAUGCUGUUGAUUGUUGAAAUGUGAAAUGUAGUCACUGUUGACCUUGUAAAUAUCUGCCAGAGAUGAAAAAAUAUUUUAAGUUAUUGUAAAUAAAGAUGUAUAAAAUUCAGUAUCAGUCUGCAAUGCAGAAACAUAUCUUAGAUGUUAAAAUACUGUGUUUGAGAGAUGUGUAAUUUACCCUUAGAUGUAUCUAGUUACAUUAAGAGUGUAAAUUUUUUUGUACAGUAUAAAAAUACAGCUCUAUUUGGCUUUUAACUGGA